AACACGGAAAGAGCUGGCUUGCGAGCUCCCUGCUUAACAGAAGGCUCAGUUGCCCAAGUGACGAAGGCAUUGUGGGGCACGAACCAGGCUUUGGUGAAUUUAUCUCAUUAUACACCAGGAGUUAUAAUUUAAAAACCAGUGUCAUAUAAAGAAGAAAAAAGAUAUGGUGAGAUACAAUACCAUUAACACUUCUUCAGAAACGGAUUUUAAAGCAGAACUUCCAUGACUGUGAAAUCCAACCGGGUGCGCGACCACGAGGAAGGAUGGCGAGGGAGGAAACCGCGCUUUGUUGUUGAGGUGAGCCGGGUGCGCGACCAUAAGGAAGGAUGGCGAGGGAGGAAACCGCGCUUUGUUCUUGAGGUGAGCCGGGUGCGCGACCACGAGGAAGGAUGGCGAGGGAGGAAACCGCGCUUUGUUGGUGAGGUGAACCGCGUGCACGAUCCCGAGGAAGUAUUGCCAGGGAGGAAACCGCGCUUUGUUCUUGAGGUGAGCCGGGUGCGCGACCAUGAGGAAGGAUGGCGAGGGAGGAAACCGCGCUUUGUUGGUGAGGUGAAACGGGUGCACGAUCCCGAGGAAGUAUUGCCAGGGAGGAAACCGCGCUUUGCUGGUGAGUUAAUGAAAAUGUCAAAAGAACCUUCAAACGUGAAUGAAAAUCCUUCCACUUCCUGUGCUGUGGAGAAUUCCACUUACCGCUCUGAAACCAGUGAUUCUCAGAAGACCCUCUUUUAUUCCUCUGACCUUUCAGAUAGCCGGUGGCUGCCCUUUUAAUUUAUACUUUUCCAAGAUACUGUUAUUAUUCUCCUUAUUUUUUUUCUUACCAACUUCUGUCAUUCCUGUUCGGUAAAGUGCCCUUGUGUGAUUUAAUGUCUGGCAGUGGCCUGUGGAAACCUUUCGAGUCAAACUAUCAUCUUUUCUUCCUUGGCAAUCUCCUAUUCUUCAGGUUUUAAGCAAUGACUAGUUUUUACAUUUUCAGCACCUUAUAUAUUUAAUAGUGGAUUAAAAAUCCUGAUGUGACUUUUGCUUUUGUCAUCAUGCAUCUGUGGUUAAUGGGCCUAAUUUGUUUCGUAUUGCAGUAAUCUUUAUAAGGAGGUUAGAAAAAUUGUGCGGAGAAAACAAUUGUAAAACAAUGAAGCAGGAAGCCCUCUCCCCACAUCUUUCACAGUGUGAAAAUGCUAAGAAAUGUUAGAAGCAAAUUAGCCCUUAAAUUGUCUCCUCAUCCAGUCCCUCCUACUAUGUUAUGGAGAGAGGACACAUUUCCAGGACAAAAAUGCUUCCGCUGAGGACUGUUUCUAUACAAAAACUCACCACCUUCCACGCAGUGUCUUGUCUUAUCACUUCUGAACAGACCUUGGUGUUUGAAAGCGUUUAGAAAUUUGCUUAACUCGCCAUUUCCUGACAUAAUGAGGAAAUCAAUGUGUCUUGCCUUUCAAAAUGCGUGUGAGUUCAGAAUAAUUCAACAAGAGUAUGCGAUGAUAAGCAGAAAUGAGACUGCAAGAAUGUGCUCAUCAACUCAGAAUCAGUGAUAACUGACAGAUAAAACAAUGUUAAUUGACUAAGGGAGACCCUACAACAUUCUGUAUCUAGAGGAACAAACUUUGGCAUUUUGUUAAAGGUUGAUUUGGCAAUUUUGAGUGAUAUUCUAGGAAACACAGGUCUGCUUUGAUGCCACUAAGACUUUGAGUAGGGACACCAAUGACUUUCAGAUA